ACUUGGAAAGGAGGAGCAGCCUCGGGUGGGACUGAGCGGAUCUUCUGGUUCUAGAGCGGCCUCUGAUUGGACAAACUUGACUUAGGGACCGUGUCUGUCUGCGAUGGGGCUUGAAACUGGGCCCUCGUCAGACUGCCUUGCCCUGUUCCUGACUCAGGCCAAGGCCUGCAGCCGGGAAGAGGUUGGGGCGGCGUGAGUUAUGUGAAAAGCGCUCAGAAUACAGUAUGUCAUGUAAGAAGCUGAAAGUGUAUUUAUGGAGCUAGAGGACAAUGCUGUCCUUCCCUGGCACAAGUGGGCGUCCGAAGUUGGAUUUUUCAAAAAGAAGACCCCGGCCAGUAAAAAGUCACCAAAUAACAAAACCCCAAAACUUCUGCAGCGCUUGGCACAUCUUGUUUAUUCAGUAAGCUUUAGGGAUUAAAAGGUGGACUCCCAUUAUUGUCCCAGUUGUUUAGAAAAUAUGCCAUCGGCUGAAGCCAAACUAAAAAAGAAUAGAUGUGCCAAUUGUUUUGACUGUCCUGGCUGCAUGCACACCCUCUCUACUCGGGCCACGAGCAUCUCCACACAGCUUCCAGAUGACCCAGCCAAGACCACCAUGAAGAAAGCCUAUUACCUGGCAUGUGGAUUUUGUCGCUGGACGUCUAGAGAUGUGGGCAUGGCAGACAAAUCUGUAGCUAGUGGCGGUUGGCAGGAACCUGAAAAUCCUCACACACAACGGAUGAACAAAUUGAUUGAAUAUUACCAGCAGCUUGCUCAGAAAGAGAAGGUUGAGCGAGAUCGCAAGAAACUGGCACGACGUAGAAACUAUAUGCCUCUGGCUUUUUCGGACAAAUAUGGUCUUGGAACCAGGCUUCAGCGACCACGAGCUGGUGCAUCCAUCAGUACCCUUGCCGGACUUUCCCUUAAAGAAGGAGAGGAUCAGAAAGAGAUAAAGAUUGAGCCAGCUCAGGCUGUGGAUGAAGUGGAACCUCUACCUGAAGACUAUUAUACAAGACCAGUAAAUUUAACAGAGGUAACAACCCUUCAGCAGCGUCUGUUACAGCCUGACUUCCAGCCAGUCUGUGCUUCACAGCUCUAUCCUCGCCACAAACAUCUUCUGAUCAAACGGUCCCUGCGCUGCCGUAAAUGUGAACAUAAUUUGAGCAAGCCAGAAUUUAACCCAACGUCAAUCAAAUUCAAAAUCCAGCUGGUCGCUGUCAAUUAUAUUCCAGAAGUGAGAAUCAUGUCAAUUCCCAACCUUCGCUACAUGAAGGAGAGCCAGGUCCUCCUGACUCUUACAAAUCCAGUUGAGAACCUCACCCAUGUGACUCUCUUCGAGUGUGAGGAGGGGGACCCUGAUGAUAUCAACAGCACUGCUAAGGUGGUGGUGCCUCCCAAAGAGCUCGUUUUAGCUGGCAAGGAUGCAGCAGCAGAGUACGAUGAGUUGGCAGAACCUCAAGACUUUCAGGACGAUCCUGACAUUAUAGCCUUCAGAAAGGCCAACAAAGUGGGUAUUUUCAUCAAAGUUACACCACAGCGUGAGGAGGGUGAAGUGACCGUGUGCUUCAAGAUGAAGCAUGAUUUUAAAAACCUGGCAGCCCCCAUUCGCCCCAUUGAAGAAAGUGACCAGGGAACAGAAGUCAUCUGGCUCACCCAGCAUGUGGAACUUAGCUUGGGCCCACUUCUUCCUUAAAAGGUUCCACUGGAGGGCAGAUCCCAAAGGACAGUAUCACCGUAAACCUGCGUUAAAAUGUGGAAGCUGCUGCUUCAUUAGGCCUUGUUUAUAACGAUGUACCCAUGCACUACGGAAUUCUAUUGCUAAGAAAGUGGGAGCAUAGGCAAGGCAUUGGGAACACAGGGUAGCUGCUGUUGCUCUUGCUCUCACCCCUGUUGACACCAGUAAGUCUGUGUCUCCCUCACUGAACCCUGCACGUUGAGUAACAGCAGCAUAAUUCCAUCCUAGGAAAGGGGAUGGGUGUUCCUUGGAAUGGCAUUGUAUUUACCACCUGAGAAACUCUGUACUGUCUCUUGAUCUGAUCUCACUAAGGAUCACAAUGUCACAGAUGAAACUUAAAUGAUAACCCAAAGGUAGACCUGCUGUUAAUGAUCCAGCAUUGGUCACAAUGUACCAACUGCUUUCUGCAUUCCGUUAAAUAUCAUCUAACAGUCUAAAACAUAUCCCUUCAUUGCCAUAAUGGCUGCCAUUUUGCCAUAGAUUUCCAUAUAACUGAAAAACUGAAUUGUCACUUUAUCUUUAGUAUCAUGAUGAUUGGAAAAACCUGUGAAGUUGUUAAGGCACUCUCAUUUGCCCUCUUUUUCUAAGUGAAUACAGGACACGUAUUAGUUGUUCUUAAUUUUUUUCCCAGUAAAAUAUGGAUCUUUUAAGAAGAAUUUGAGAAGCAAACAAUUACAUGUCAUGUCAAGGGGGUAGCAGAUUCCAUUCGUUUUCAAUAUUGCCACAAUACCCAGGGAUUAAUGCUGCCACAGGGGGGCAAUCUUUAUUUGUCUUACUUCCUACCCCUUCCCUGUUCUGCCUCUUUAACUCAGUUAAGUUGUUCUGUUUGGGACCUGGAAAAGAACCCAAAGAAAACCUGAGUGGACAGGUUCAUUUCUGGAAUGCAGAAAACAUUUUAAAGGCUAGAUUUUUAGAAUAUUCUCAACUAGCAUUCUUUCCAUUGAUUUGAAGGGGAAAUUAACUAUUAUAAUCUCUUGAAUCCAAAACUGGAUAUUAAGAACUUUCCCCCUUACUAAGUUUAAGACUUUUGUCAUGUGGUGAGUCAAAUAAGACCAUUUUGAUUGUAAACCAUAAAAUAGUUCAGCAAGUAGCCCACAGUUCUGGCCUAACAGCAGACUUGCUGUUUUCACUUGGUAUCCUGGAGUUGGGUUGCUAACCUUAAUUUCUAUGAUGUUUUCUAAAAUGAAACUUGAUAAAGUAGACCACCAGCUGCACCGUGUUUUCUGUAAAAGUAUUGUUAGUAAGUGGCCAAGAGACUUGAGGAAAAUACAGAUUUUUUGUUUACCUUGGUCUUGUUUUAAGUCUUAAAAAAUUAAAGAUAACAUUAUAAUGUAGAAUACAGAUGGGACAUAGUCCUUGUAAGCUUCCCUUGAAAAUGUUUUAAAUAUUUAGGAAGCUUUUAAAAGACACUAAAUUGUACUCUAAAAGACACUAAAUUGUACUAAUUGUACAAAGGUCAAGCCAAUUUUAUGAAACAGUCCUACAGAGUAAUAUAUGUGAUGCAGUGUAAGAAGGAAAAUACUCAUCUCUAACAUUAUGGUAAUAACAUUUAGCCUCUUAGGAGUUGGAGCAGGGGGAUGGGUAAUUACAGAUUUGCAGACUAUAGAAAGAGUUUCAUUUUUUUGUGACCCCACAGAGUCUCAAAUUUUUAUUUCACUACCUGCUAGAGCCUACUGUGAAAUCACUGCUCCAUAUUUGCCAGUGGAGGAAAUGGGCAUAGAGUAGAGAAUAGCUUCAUAUGUUUACACGUUUGCAUAGACUACACACAUGUCAUGCGUUUAUGGCAGGUAGCUGGUAUUUAUUCCCCAAAGUAAUAAUGUUGAAGUAUGGGUCUCAUCAUUCCCAUACACAGAAACACAAAACACUUUGAUCAUAAACUUUUUUCUUCAGAAGCCAAACUAACUUGCAGAAUAAUAGAGCCACUGGUUUAAUGUUUCCUCAAGAUAGGUUUUAGUGUAAGCUAGUAUUCUGUGUGUUCGUAGAAAUGAUUCAAUACCUGCAGCUGGUGAAUUAGGAAUUGUAUUUGUUGCCUUUUUUAUAUUAGAUGAGGUGCAAAAAUUUUAAUGCUAGUCAGUAUGCACCACCACAGGAAAGUUAGAUCCCAUUAGCACUUGAAACUACAGCUUUGGAAACUUAGGCUAAGUUAAUUUGGAUUUGUUACUUGAUUCACCUACUGACCUUUUCUUUUGUUUGAAGUGCUUAUCAGCAUAAUGAGCUAAGUGUCAUGCAUAUUUGUGAAGAAACACCCUUUUUGGUCCCUUUUGGGACAGAGAGGUACUCCUUGAUCUUUAUGAAUGACAGGUUACUGUUUUGCCUUAUUGCUUAACUUAAUGUAGUGAAAUAAAGCAGACAAAGCUUGAGCGUGUCUUUUGUUUGCUCUCAUGUAGAUACUAAGUAGCAUGGCUCAGAGCCAAAAGACAAGCGUGAAGUUAAGAGAGUUGGCUAAGAGAGUUGGUGGGGCAUGCUCCCUUCCAUUCCUUAAAUGAAGUAAUCUAAAAUCUCUUAGCAGGUUAGUUCACCAUAAUAUAUAAGUAGAUGUUGCUUUGAGCUUCUUAUAUACAUAUUCACAGAACCAUUAUAUAAAUGUUGUUAGACCUCUACCAGUUUUUAUCCUGGGUCAUUGCUUCUAAAGAUAUCCUUUACAAUAUACACAGUGGUCUGACUCCA